AUGUUUUGUUGCUUAGGAUAUGAAUGGCUGAGCGGAGGCUGUAAAACCUGGCACUCUGCUUGGGUUAUCAAUACUCUGGCUGACCAUCGUCAUCGUGGGACUGACUUUGGUGGAAGUCCUUGGUUACUUAUCAUUACUGUGUUUCUGAGAAGUUAUAAAUUUGCCAUCUCCCUCUGCACAAGUUACCUUUGUGUGUCUUUCCUGAAGACUAUCUUCCCGUCUCAAAAUGGACAUGAUGGAUCCACGGAUGUACAGCAGAGAGCCAGGAGGUCCAACCGCCGUAGACAGGAAGGAAUUAAAAUUGUCCUGGAAGACAUCUUUACUUUAUGGAGACAGGUGGAAACCAAAGUUCGAGCUAAAAUCCGUAAGAUGAAGGUGACAACAAAAGUCAACCGUCAUGACAAAAUCAAUGGAAAGAGGAAGACCGCCAAAGAACAUCUGAGGAAACUAAGCAUGAAAGAACGUGAGCACGGAGAAAAGGAGAGGCAGGUGUCAGAGGCAGAGGAAAAUGGGAAAUUGGAUAUGAAAGAAAUACACACCUACAUGGAAAUGUUUCAACGUGCGCAAGCGUUGCGGCGGCGGGCAGAGGACUACUACAGAUGCAAAAUCACCCCUUCUGCAAGAAAGCCUCUUUGCAACCGGGUCAGAAUGGCGGCAGUGGAGCAUCGUCAUUCUUCAGGAUUGCCCUACUGGCCCUACCUCACAGCUGAAACUUUAAAAAACAGGAUGGGCCACCAGCCACCUCCUCCAACUCAACAACAUUCUAUAAUUGAUAACUCCCUGAGCCUCAAGACACCUUCCGAGUGUCUGCUCACUCCCCUUCCACCCUCAGCUCUACCCUCAGCGGAUGAUAAUCUCAAGACACCUGCGGAGUGUCUGCUCUAUCCCCUUCCACCCUCAGCGGAUGAUAAUCUCAAGACACCUCCCGAGUGUCUGCUCACUCCCCUUCCACCCUCAGCUCCACCCUCAGUGGAUGAUAAUCUCAAGACACCUCCCGAGUGUGUCUGCUCACUCCCCUUCCACCCUCAGCGGAUGAUAAUCUCAAGAAACUAAGGAAGAAUAAAUAAAUAAUAUAAAAAUAAAA